GUAGUCAUCCAUUUAGCAGAUAGUAAAUUAAAAUGUUGUAUAAUCCACUGGAGUUCAAUAUUGGGUCAUUUUCUUCAAAGAAGAGAGAGGUAUUAAUUAGUUUGUUGCUUGGAGGCUUCAUUCCCUUUGCUGUUGUAACAAACGGUUCCUGGGCACUCUCAGGCCCUGACUGAUUAACUUGCAUAGCUUCCUUUUGAUAGCUCUCCUUCUGACACACAUGGUUAAACAGGAGAGAAUGAGGUGGAGGAGUAGAAAAAGAAGAAGAAGAAAAAAAAACUUGGCUCUUUUCUUGAUAAGUGAAAGCAAAUAAAUGCAACACAUCAGCAAACAAAAGUGAAAUACACUGCCCAAGUCGUCCAUCUUAGCAAUAGAGUUUCUUUAAGCCAAAAAUCAAAUGUAGUGGCGGUAUUUCACUGUUGGAGUUGCAAACAACUGAGAAAUGACAAAAGCUUUUUAAGGCCACGGUCUUUGCAAGAGGGAAAGAUGUCUUUCUGUUGAAACUGAAAAAUUAAGAUCGAUUAUAGCUGAGGAAUAAAACCUCAGUGUGUUGAAUUCAAGGGACAGAAUUGUUGAUAUAGAUUCUUAAGUCAUCAUAAGUAUCCAAAAGUGGAAACUUAACAAAGUGUGGUUUCCCCGGUAUAAUUUUCACAUCAGUGGUUUUUUUCUCCCCCAACCUGGUCUUUCUCUUCAAAGGAGAUUUACUUUUCCAAAAAGCAUUUUUAAUUAUGUUGAAGUAAAGGCAAUACCUUUUCUUUUAACUUUAAAUUUCAAACUACUUUUAAAGAAAAGUUGCAAAAAUGGAACGGAGAAUUUUCACAUAUCCCUGCCCUAGCCUCCCUCAGUAUUAAAAUCUUAACUGGAGUGCAAUUAUCAGAACCCAGAAAUUAACAUUGAUAUAAUACCAAUAAUUAAACAAAAAUCUUAUUCAAAUUCUACCAGUUUUUUCAUCAAUAUUUCAUUGUUAUUAUUCUCCAGGAUUCUGUUCAGGAUCCCAUGUCACAUUUUGUUGUUAUUUCUCCUUAGUCUCCUGAAAUCUGUAACAGUUUCUCAUCUUUCCUUAACUUUUAAGACCUUAUAUUUUUGAAGAGUAUAGAAUACUUAUUUUGCCAAAUUCCCCUCAAUUUGGGCUUGUCUGGUGUUUUCUCAUGCUUGGUUUGAGGUUAUGUGUUUUUGGCAAGAAUUCCACAGAAAUGAUGUGUUCUUCUCAGCACAUCAUGUCAUGGGAUUUGUGAUGCCAAUAUUUUUUAUUAGUGGUGGUGUUGAUCAUGACCACUUGAUUAAGGUGGUUUCUGCUGGGUUCUCCACUUUAUAGUUAGUAUCUUUUCUCCUACUGUUAAGAAAGAUCUUGGGGGACAUGCUUUAAGACUGUGCAAAUCCUGUUUCUCUUUAGACUGUGAACAAAUGAUUUCAGCAUACAUCCAUGGAUUUUGAUUCUAGUUACAAUUGUUAUUAUGGUGUUUGCUUAAUGGUGAUUUUCCACUUCCUUCUUUCUUUCAACAUGUAUUAAUUGGGAUUCUACAGCCAUGGAAGAGCUGUCUUUCUCUCCUAUUUAGAUAAUAGAUUAUUUAUAUCCAUGUGUAUGAACUUAUAUAUAUUUAUUUGGUUUUAUGGGUCAUAUUCUAAUAUUAUUAUUUAACUUGUUUAAUUUGUUCCAGCUUUGGCUGUUAGGAGCUUAUUUUCAUUUAGUGUUUGUGCUCUCUUAUUAAGCCCUUAUUUAUUUUUUUGAACACUUUCUUACUUUUUUGCUUCACACUAUAUUCUAAGCUUAUUUUUUUCCUCCUGCUCUAGUCCUGAAAUCAAUCACUUGUCCAAGCUUUUUUCUUUCUUUCUUUCUUUCUUUUUUUUAAAUCAGAGAAUGGUGUUUAGAAACUGAGAUCUUCAUGCUAGAUGUGCUUAUUACUACUGGGAUGUCAUUGCUCUAAGCCUUCUCAGCAGGCAGAGCCAGGAAAUAUAUGCAUAUGAAUAACCUGCACAUAUACACACCUCUAUAUUUCUUUAUCUAUAUGUCUAUAUAGAUAUUUAAAGCCAUUUGUACUAUACAAUUUAUACUAAAUACUGUAAACUCAGGGUUCACUUUUAGCUUUUUCCUGUCUUUAUUUGUAAUUUAUUUCUCAAAUAGUGAGAAAUCUGCUUAUUUUCCAUGAUAUGUUUACUUCUUUGUUUGAUUCUAGUGAACACAUAGUUUUAGAAUUGCUAUCCUAUGCCCCUGCGAGAAACAUAUUUACUGACUAAAUUCUAGCAUUUAUGCAUUUGUAUUUGUCUUUAGCUUCAUGGUAUCCAGUCAAGAUACUGUUUUCUGUAGUUAUUUAGGUUAGUGUUACUAUUCCCCAUCCUUUCAGUGUAGUUUUGUAACUCAUUUGUAACAGGCUUAUUUGUUAUUUUUGUAUUGCAUUUUGGAUCCUCAUCAUUGUUAGUUUUAGUUGUUGAUUGCUUAGGGGCAUGUGAAAAAUAUGAAUCAUAACUGUGGUUCUAAGAGCCAGAGCUUUACAAAAUGAUGCACCCAAGGCAGUAUCUGUCACUCCAUCCUGUCUUGAUACACAUAACCAUUUCCGUCUUCUUUCCAGCUCUUUGACACCUGCCCUCUGUAGAUAGUUUCUUUAGUUUCUGGUGAGUUCCUUCCAUAUUUUCUUUGUACAAAUGGGCAGUUAUGUAUGUGUUUUCUUAUAAUCACUUUUCUUAUACAAGGAGUAACAUAAUAUAGAUACUCUUUUGCACUUAGCUUUUUUUACCUUAACAGUACAUCCUGGAAGUUAGCCUGUAACAAUUCAAAGAGAUCUUCAUUAAUCUUUUUUACAGCAUUAUUGUACUCCAUUUUGGAGAUAUAUGACAAUAUCUUCUUUAUGUACCACUUUCCCUUGCAGAUAGGUGUGCCACGUUAACAGACUAAGGAAGUUUAAUAUUAUUAUAAAAGAAGCAAGAAUAAGACAGUUAAAAAAAAAAAAGACUUGGACAAAGCUGCUACAUGUAGCUGCUGCAUUUAGGAUCAAUCCAGGUAGAACAAAAUAGAAGUUAAUCAGAUGGUCUGGACCACCAAAAGUUUUUGACUUUUACAACUUACUAGUACGGUGAAUUUGGGUGGUGUUUGCAUUGCUCAGUCACAGAAAAUCCCACGUGAACCAAGACCUGGAGAAUUUGAAAAAAUUAUCAAACGCCUGCUAGAAACACCUAAUGCUCGAGCAGUGAUUAUGUUUGCCAAUGAGGAUGACAUCAGGAGGAUAUUGGAAGCAGCAAAAAAACUAAACCAAAGUGGGCAUUUUCUCUGGAUUGGCUCAGAUAGUUGGGGAUCCAAAAUAGCACCUGUCUAUCAGCAAGAGGAGAUUGCAGAAGGGGCUGUGACAAUUUUGCCCAAACGAGCAUCAAUUGAUGGAUUUGAUCGAUACUUUAGAAGCCGAACUCUUGCCAAUAAUCGAAGAAAUGUGUGGUUUGCAGAAUUCUGGGAGGAGAAUUUUGGCUGCAAGUUAGGAUCACAUGGGAAAAGGAACAGUCAUAUAAAGAAAUGCACAGGGCUGGAGCGAAUUGCUCGGGAUUCAUCUUAUGAACAGGAAGGAAAGGUCCAAUUUGUAAUUGAUGCUGUAUAUUCCAUGGCUUACGCCCUGCACAAUAUGCACAAAGAUCUCUGCCCUGGAUACAUUGGCCUUUGUCCACGAAUGAGUACCAUUGAUGGGAAAGAGCUACUUGGUUAUAUUCGGGCUGUAAAUUUUAAUGGCAGUGCUGGCACUCCUGUCACUUUUAAUGAAAACGGAGAUGCUCCUGGACGUUAUGAUAUCUUCCAGUAUCAAAUAACCAACAAAAGCACAGAGUACAAAGUCAUCGGCCACUGGACCAAUCAGCUUCAUCUAAAAGUGGAAGACAUGCAGUGGGCUCAUAGAGAACAUACUCACCCGGCGUCUGUCUGCAGCCUGCCGUGUAAGCCAGGGGAGAGGAAGAAAACGGUGAAAGGGGUCCCUUGCUGCUGGCACUGUGAACGCUGUGAAGGUUACAACUACCAGGUGGAUGAGCUGUCCUGUGAACUUUGCCCUCUGGAUCAGAGACCCAACAUGAACCGCACAGGCUGCCAGCUUAUCCCCAUCAUCAAAUUGGAGUGGCAUUCUCCCUGGGCUGUGGUGCCUGUGUUUGUUGCAAUAUUGGGAAUCAUCGCCACCACCUUUGUGAUCGUGACCUUUGUCCGCUAUAAUGACACACCUAUCGUGAGGGCUUCAGGACGCGAACUUAGUUACGUGCUCCUAACGGGGAUUUUUCUCUGUUAUUCAAUCACGUUUUUAAUGAUUGCAGCACCAGAUACAAUCAUAUGCUCCUUCCGACGGGUCUUCCUAGGACUUGGCAUGUGUUUCAGCUAUGCAGCCCUUCUGACCAAAACAAACCGUAUCCACCGAAUAUUUGAGCAGGGGAAGAAAUCUGUCACAGCGCCCAAGUUCAUUAGUCCAGCAUCUCAGCUGGUGAUCACCUUCAGCCUCAUCUCCGUCCAGCUCCUUGGAGUGUUUGUCUGGUUUGUUGUGGAUCCCCCCCACAUCAUCAUUGACUAUGGAGAGCAGCGGACACUAGAUCCAGAGAAGGCCAGGGGAGUGCUCAAGUGUGACAUUUCUGAUCUCUCACUCAUUUGUUCACUUGGAUACAGUAUCCUCUUGAUGGUCACUUGUACUGUUUAUGCCAUUAAAACGAGAGGUGUCCCAGAGACUUUCAAUGAAGCCAAACCUAUUGGAUUUACCAUGUAUACCACCUGCAUCAUUUGGUUAGCUUUCAUCCCCAUCUUUUUUGGUACAGCCCAGUCAGCAGAAAAGAUGUACAUCCAGACAACAACACUUACUGUCUCCAUGAGUUUAAGUGCUUCAGUAUCUCUGGGCAUGCUCUAUAUGCCCAAGGUUUAUAUUAUAAUUUUUCAUCCAGAACAGAAUGUUCAAAAACGCAAGAGGAGCUUCAAGGCUGUGGUGACAGCUGCCACCAUGCAAAGCAAACUGAUCCAAAAAGGAAAUGACAGACCAAAUGGCGAGGUGAAAAGUGAACUCUGUGAGAGUCUUGAAACCAACACUUCCUCUACCAAGACAACAUAUAUCAGUUACAGCAAUCAUUCAAUCUGAAACAGGGAAAUGGCACAAUCUGAAGAGAUGUGGUAUAUGAUCUUAAAUGAUGAACAUGAGACCGCAAAAAUUCACUCCUGGAGAUCUCCGUAGACUACAAUCAAUCAAAUCAAUAGUCAGUCUUGUAAGGAACAAAAAUUAGCCAUGAGCCAAAAGUAUCAAUAAACGGGGAGUGAAGAAACCCGUUUUAUACAAUAAAACCAAUGAGUGUCAAGCUAAAGUAUUGCUUAUUCAUGAGCAGUUAAAACAAAUCACAAAAGGAAAACUAAUGUUAGCUCGUGAAAAAAAAUGCUGUUGAAAUAAAUAAUGUCUGAUGUUAUUCUUGUAUUUUUCUGUGAUUGUGAGAACUCCCGUUCCUGUCCCACAUUGUUUAACUUGUAUAAGACAAUGAGUCUGUUUCUUGUAAUGGCUGACCAGAUUGAAGCCCUGGGUUGUGCUAAAAAUAAAUGCAAUGAUUGAUGCAUGCAAUUUUUUAUACAAAUAAUUUAUUUCUAAUAAUAAAGGAAUGUUUUGCAAAUGUU